AUAAAGCAGAAUGUCUGCUCUCUGUGCCCAGACGUGAGCAGGCCUCCCUCCACCUGUCUUCUCAGAGCAGGUAAUGGCAAGCAUGGCUGCCGUGCUCACCUGGGCUCUGGCUCUUCUUUCAGCGUUUUCGGCCACCCAGGCACGGAAAGGCUUCUGGGACUACUUCAGCCAGACCAGCGGGGACAAAGGCAGGGUGGAGCAGAUCCAUCAGCAGAAGAUGGCUCGCGAGCCCGCGACCCUGAAAGACAGCCUUGAGCAAGACCUCAACAAUAUGAACAAGUUCCUGGAAAAGCUGAGGCCUCUGAGUGGGAGCGAGGCUCCUCGGCUCCCACAGGACCCGGUGGGCAUGCGGCGGCAGCUGCAGGAGGAGUUGGAGGAGGUGAAGGCUCGCCUCCAGCCCUACAUGGCAGAGGCGCACGAGCUGGUGGGCUGGAAUUUGGAGGGCUUGCGGCAGCAACUGAAGCCCUACACGAUGGAUCUGAUGGAGCAGGUGGCCCUGCGCGUGCAGGAGCUGCAGGAGCAGUUGCGCGUGGUGGGGGAAGACACCAAGGCCCAGUUGCUGGGGGGCGUGGACGAGGCUUGGGCUUUGCUGCAGGGACUGCAGAGCCGCGUGGUGCACCACACCGGCCGCUUCAAAGAGCUCUUCCACCCAUACGCCGAGAGCCUGGUGAGCGGCAUCGGGCGCCACGUGCAGGAGCUGCACCGCAGUGUGGCUCCGCACGCCCCCGCCAGCCCCGCGCGCCUCAGUCGCUGCGUGCAGGUGCUCUCCCGGAAGCUCACGCUCAAGGCCAAGGCCCUGCACGCACGCAUCCAGCAGAACCUGGACCAGCUGCGCGAAGAGCUCAGCAGAGCCUUUGCAGGCACUGGGACUGAGGAAGGGGCCGGCCCGGACCCCCAGAUGCUCUCCGAGGAGGUGCGCCAGCGACUUCAGGCUUUCCGCCAGGACACCUACCUGCAGAUAGCUGCCUUCACUCGCGCCAUCGACCAGGAGACUGAGGAGGUCCAGCAGCAGCUGGCGCCACCUCCACCAGGCCACAGUGCCUUCGCCCCAGAGUUUCAACAAACAGACAGUGGCAAGGUUCUGAGCAAGCUGCAGGCCCGUCUGGAUGACCUGUGGGAAGACAUCACUCACAGCCUUCAUGACCAGGGCCACAGCCAUCUGGGGGACCCCUGAGGAUCUACCUGCCCAGGCCCAUUCCCAGCUCCUUGUCUGGGGAGCCUUGGCUCUGAGCCUCUAGCAUGGUUCAGUCCUUGAAAGUGGCCUGUUGGGUGGAGGGUGGAAGGUCCUGUGCAGGACAGGGAGGCCACCAAAGGGGCUGCUGUCUCCUGCACAUCCAGCCUCCUGCGACUCCCCAAUCUGGAUGCAUUACAUUCACCAGGCUUUGCAAACCCAGCCUCCCAGUGCUCAUUUGGGAAUGCUCAUGAGUUACUCCAUUCAAGGGUGAGGGAGUAGGGAGGGAGAGGCACCAUGCAUGUGGGUGAUUAUCUGCAAGCCUGUUUGCCGUGAUGCUGGAAGCCUGUGCCACUACAUCCUGGAGUUUGGCUCUAGUCACUUCUGGCUGCCUGGUGGCCACUGCUACAGCUGGUCCACAGAGAGGAGCACUUGUCUCCCCAGGGCUGCCAUGGCAGCUAUCAGGGGAAUAGAAGGGAGAAAGAGAAUAUCAUGGGGAGAACAUGUGAUGGUGUGUGAAUAUCCCUGCUGGCUCUGAUGCUGGUGGGUACGAAAGGUGUGGGCUGUGAUAGGAGAGGGCAGAGCCCAUGUUUCCUGACAUAGCUCUACACCUAAAUAAGGGACUGAACCCUCCCAACUGUGGGAGCUCCUUAAACCCUCUGGGGAGCAUACUGUGUGCUCUCCCCAUCUCCAGCCCCUCCCUCUGGGUUCCCAAGUUGAAGCCUAGACUUCUGGCUCAAAUGAAAUAGAUGUUUAUGAUAGAA